ACCAGCAACCUCGCCCCUCCCUGCGGAAAACCGAUGAGAGGCAGGGCCAAGCCGAAGCGAUGGCGGCCUAUCCGGAGAGCUGCGUGGACACUACGGUGCUGGACUUCGUCGCAGACCUGUCCCUGGCCUCCCCGAGACGCCCUCUCCUCUGCGACUUCGCACCCGGGGUCUCCUUGGGGGACCCAGCCCUUGCGCUCCGAGAGGGAAGACCCAGGAGGAUGGCGCGGUUUGAAGAGGGGGACCCAGAAGAAGAGGAGUGCGAAGUGGACCAGGGGGACGGAGAAGAGGAGGAGGAAGAGGAGCGCGGAAGAGGUGUCUCCCUAUUAGGCCGCCCCAAGAGGAAAAGGGUGAUCACCUACGCCCAGCGCCAGGCCGCCAACAUCCGCGAAAGGAAGCGGAUGUUCAACCUCAACGAGGCCUUUGACCAGCUGCGGAGGAAGGUGCCCACGUUUGCUUACGAGAAAAGGCUGUCCCGGAUCGAGACCCUCCGCCUGGCCAUCGUCUAUAUCUCCUUCAUGACCGAGCUCUUGGAGAGCUGUGAGAAGAAGGAAAGCGGCUGAGCCUGGUGUGGAGAGUCUGCCCUUCCUCGUCUGGUAGUGCUGGGGUGUGUCAGGACCGGGCACUGGGUGAGGCUAAAGGG